GAGGAUGUUGAUUGUUGGAACACACACCUGUCCAGGUGCAGGGGAGCUGGAGGCUCUGUGAGAGGAGGGCCAGCUCAGCCACAGCAGGAGGACUGACAGGGGCCUGAUGGAGGAGUUUGUGGGGCUGCGUGAAGGCUCCUCAGGGAACCCUGUGACUCUGCAGGAGCUGUGGGGCCCCUGUCCCCGCAUCCGCCGAGGCAUCCGAGGUGGCCUGGAGUGGCUGAAGCAGAAGCUCUUCCGCCUGGGCGAGGACUGGUACUUCCUGAUGACCCUCGGGGUGCUCAUGGCCCUGGUCAGCUGUGCCAUGGACUUGGCUGUUGAGAGUGUGGUCCGAGCGCACCAGUGGCUGUACAGGGAGAUUGGGGACAGCCACCUGCUCCGGUAUCUCUCCUGGACUGUGUACCCUGUGGCCCUCGUCUCUUUCUCUUCAGGCUUCUCUCAGAGCAUCACACCCUCCUCUGGAGGUUCUGGAAUCCCGGAGGUGAAGACCAUGUUGGCGGGUGUGGUCUUGGAGGACUACCUGGAUAUCAAGAACUUUGGGGCCAAAGUGGUGGGCCUCUCCUGCACCCUGGCCUGUGGCAGCACCCUCUUCCUCGGGAAAGUGGGCCCUUUCGUGCACCUGUCUGUGAUGAUGGCUGCCUACCUGGGCCGUGUGCGCACCACGACCAUCGGGGAGCCUGAGAACAAGAGCAAGCAAAACGAAAUGCUGGUGGCAGCGGCGGCAGUGGGCGUGGCCACAGUCUUUGCAGCUCCCUUCAGCGGCGUCCUGUUCAGCAUCGAGGUCAUGUCUUCCCACUUCUCUGUCUGGGAUUACUGGAGGGGCUUCUUUGCGGCCACCUGCGGGGCCUUCAUGUUCCGGCUCCUGGCGGUCUUCAACAGCGAGCAGGAGACCAUCACCUCCCUCUACAAGACCAGUUUCCGGGUGGACGUUCCCUUCGACCUGCCUGAGAUCUUCUUUUUUGUGGCGCUGGGGGGUCUCUGUGGCAUCCUGGGCAGCGCUUACCUCUUCUGUCAGCGAAUCUUCUUUGGCUUCAUCAGGAACAAUAGGUUCAGCUCCAAACUGCUGGCCACCAGCAAGCCUGUGUACUCCGCUCUGGCCACCUUGGUUCUCGCCUCCAUCACCUACCCACCCAGCGCCGGCCGCUUCCUAGCUUCUCGGCUGUCCAUGAAGCAGCAUCUGGACUCGCUGUUCGACAACCACUCCUGGGCGCUGAUGACCCAGAACUCCAGCCCACCCUGGCCCGAGGAGCUCGACCCCCAGCACCUGUGGUGGGAAUGGUACCACCCGCGGUUCACCAUCUUUGGGACCCUUGCCUUCUUCCUGGUUAUGAAGUUCUGGAUGCUGAUUCUGGCCACCACCAUCCCCAUGCCUGCCGGGUACUUCAUGCCCAUCUUUGUCUAUGGAGCUGCUAUCGGGCGCCUCUUUGGGGAGACUCUCUCUUUUAUCUUCCCUGAGGGCAUCGUGGCUGGAGGGAUCACCAAUCCCAUCAUGCCAGGGGGGUAUGCUCUGGCAGGGGCUGCAGCCUUCUCAGGGGCUGUGACCCACACCAUCUCCACGGCGCUGCUGGCCUUCGAGGUGACCGGCCAGAUAGUGCAUGCACUGCCCGUGCUGAUGGCGGUGCUGGCAGCCAACGCCAUUGCACAGAGCUGCCAGCCCUCCUUCUAUGAUGGCACCGUCAUUGUCAAGAAGCUGCCAUACCUGCCACGGAUUCUGGGCCGCAACAUCGGUUCCCACCGCGUGAGGGUGGAGCACUUCAUGAACCACAGCAUCACCACACUGGCCAAGGACAUGCCACUGGAGGAGGUGGUCAAGGUUGUGACCUCCACAGACGUGGCCAAGUAUCCCCUGGUGGAGAGCACAGAGUCCCAGAUCCUGGUGGGCAUAGUGCGAAGGGCCCAGCUGGUGCAGGCCCUGAAGGCUGAGCCUCCUUCCUGGGCUCCUGGACACCAGCAGUGUCUCCAGGACAUCUUGGCUGCAGGCUGCCCCACAGAACCAGUGACCCUGAAGCUGUCCCCAGAGACUUCCCUGCAUGAGGCACACAACCUCUUUGAGCUGUUGAACCUUCAUUCCCUCUUUGUGACGUCGCGGGGCAGAGCUGUGGGCUGCGUGUCCUGGGUGGAGAUGAAGAAAGCAAUUUCCAACCUGACAAAUCCGCCAGCCCCAAAGUGAGCCGGCCCAGCAAGAUGAAACAGGGCACCCCAGCUGACCUGGUACUGAGGUUGGGCUGAGACCCUGCUUCUCUUCCCCCAUCACCACCUGCCCCUCCCUCCAGCCCAGCUCCAUUCUUUGGCAUAACAGGCAACUUUAACCUAGCCCAGAAGAGGAUGGCUCAUCCUGGGUGGGACGAUGGCUCCUGCCUUGAAAGACAAAAAUCCCACCUUGGGCAGAGCUGAGUGUGAGAAGAUGGAAAACCAGUAUCUGCCAGUUGCUCAGUGACUGGCCAUCACAUUAAUGAAUGAUGAGAUUGGAGUACACUGUCACCAAGGGCAGGCACAGAUGCCUUCUGGGGUUGUCUGGUUCCCAGUGAGAGGCUCCUGAGAAAAAUAAAGCUGGUUCCCAGA